CAGCCUCCUGAAUGAUGCCAGCCCAGUAUGCUCUAACCUCCAGCCUGGUUCUCCUGGUGCUGCUGAGCACAGCCAGAGCAGGCCCCUUCUCUUCACGGUCCAAUGUGACACUGCCAGCCCCCCGGCCCCCUCCCCAGCCAGGGGGCCACACAGUGGGGGCUGGAGUGGGAAGCCCCUCUUCUCAGCUUUACGAGCACACAGUGGAAGGAGGGGAGAAGCAGGUGGUAUUCACCCACCGCAUUAACCUGCCCCCUUCCACUGGCUGUGGCUGUCCCCCAGGCACCGAGCCCCCAGUCCUUGCUUCAGAGGUACAGGCCCUGAGGGUCCGUCUAGAGAUCCUGGAGGAGUUGGUGAAGGGGCUCAAGGAACAGUGCACUGGGGGAUGUUGUCCUGCCUCUGCCCAAGCUGGCACAGGUCAGACAGAUGUGCGGACCCUCUGCAGUCUCCAUGGUGUGUUUGAUCUGAGCCGCUGCACCUGUUCCUGUGAGCCAGGCUGGGGUGGGCCCACCUGCUCAGACCCCACAGAUGCUGAGAUCCCUCCCUCUUCCCCACCCUCAGCCUCGGGGUCCUGCCCAGAUGACUGCAAUGAUCAGGGUCGCUGUGUCCGUGGUCGUUGCGUGUGCUUUCCCGGCUACACUGGCCCCAGCUGUGGCUGGCCAUCCUGUCCCGGGGACUGCCAAGGCCGUGGGCGCUGCGUGCAGGGCGUGUGUGUGUGCCGGGCAGGCUUCUCAGGCCCCGACUGCAGCCAGCGCUCCUGCCCUCGAGGUUGCAGCCAGAGGGGACGCUGUGAGGGUGGGCGCUGCGUGUGUGACCCAGGCUACACUGGUGACGACUGUGGCAUGAGGAGCUGCCCUCGCGGUUGCAGUCAGAGGGGGCGCUGUGAGAAUGGGCGCUGCGUGUGUAACCCCGGCUACACUGGCGAGGACUGUGGGGUGAGGAGCUGCCCUCGGGGCUGCAGCCAGCGGGGACGCUGCAAGGACGGGCGCUGCGUGUGUGACCCCGGCUACACUGGCGAGGACUGUGGUACGCGGAGCUGCCCCUGGGACUGUGGCGAGGGCGGGCGCUGCGUGGACGGCCGCUGCGUGUGCUGGCCCGGGUACACAGGCGAGGACUGCAGCACGCGGACAUGUCCGAGGGACUGCCGGGGCCGCGGGCGCUGCGAGGACGGCGAAUGCAUUUGCGACACGGGCUACAGCGGGGACGACUGCGGCGUGCGCAGCUGCCCUGGCGACUGCAACCAAAGGGGCCGCUGCGAGGACGGCCGCUGCGUGUGCUGGCCGGGGUACACUGGAACCGAUUGCGGCUCGCGCGCCUGCCCACGCGACUGUAGAGGUCGCGGGCGCUGCGAGAACGGCGUGUGUGUUUGCAAUGCGGGCUACAGCGGCGAGGACUGCGGUGUGCGCAGCUGUCCUGGGGACUGUCGUGGCCGGGGCCGCUGUGAGAGUGGCCGCUGCAUGUGUUGGCCGGGGUACACAGGCCGGGACUGCGGCACGCGCGCCUGUCCUGGCGACUGUCGCGGGCGCGGGCGCUGCGUGGAUGGCCGCUGCGUGUGCAACCCGGGCUUCACCGGUGAGGACUGUGGGAGCCGUCGCUGUCCCGGGGACUGCCGUGGGCACGGCCUUUGCGAGGAUGGCGUGUGCGUGUGUGACGCAGGCUACUCAGGGGAAGACUGCAGCACGCGCAGCUGCCCCGGGGGCUGCCGAGGCCGCGGCCAGUGCCUAGAUGGGCGGUGUGUGUGCGAGGACGGCUACUCUGGCGAGGAUUGCGGUGUGAGGCAGUGCCCGAAUGACUGCAGCCAGCACGGCGUGUGCCAGGACGGUGUGUGCAUCUGUUGGGAAGGCUACGUGAGUGAGGACUGCAGCAUCCGCACCUGCCCCUCCAACUGCCACGGGAGGGGCCGCUGUGAGGAAGGGCGCUGCCUGUGCGACCCAGGCUACACCGGCCCUACCUGUGCCACCCGCAUGUGCCCGGCUGACUGCCGGGGACGUGGGCGGUGUGUGCAAGGAGUGUGCCUGUGCCACGUGGGCUAUGGCGGUGAGGACUGCGGGCAGGAAGAGCCUCCAGCCAGCGCCUGCCCUGGAGGCUGCGGGCCCCGGGAACUGUGCCGGGCAGGCCAGUGUGUGUGUGUAGAGGGCUUCCGAGGCCCUGACUGUGCCAUCCAGACAUGCCCAGGGGACUGCCGUGGCCGAGGAGAGUGUCACGAUGGCAGCUGUGUCUGCAAAGAUGGGUAUGCUGGCGAAGACUGCGGAGAAGAGGUGCCAACCAUUGAGGGCAUGAGGAUGCAUCUCUUGGAGGAGACAACAGUUCGGACAGAGUGGACCCCGGCUCCUGGCCCCGUGGAUGCCUAUGAAAUUCAGUUCAUCCCCACGACAGAGGGGGCGAGCCCCCCAUUCACAGCACGGGUUCCAAGCUCUGCCUCAGCCUAUGACCAGAGAGGACUGGCCCCUGGACAGGAGUACCAGGUCACUGUCCGAGCCCUUCGAGGGACCAGCUGGGGCCUUCCUGCCUCCAAGACCAUCACCACCAUGAUCGAUGGGCCCCAGGACCUCCGAGUGGUGGCUGUGACACCGACAACACUGGAGCUUGGCUGGCUGCGUCCCCAGGCUGAGGUGGACCGAUUUGUGGUGUCCUACGUCAGUGCCGGCAACCAGAGGGUGAGGCUGGAAGUGCCCCCUGAAGCAGACGGGACGCUGCUGACUGACCUGAUGCCAGGCGUAGAAUAUGUGGUGACUGUCACAGCGGAGCGGGGCCGGGCAGUCAGCUACCCAGCUUCUGUCAGGGCCAACACAGGGUCCUCACCCUUGGGCCUCUUGGGGACUACCGAUGAGCCUCCUCCCUCAGGCCCCUCGACGACGCAAGGGGCCCAGGCUCCUCUCCUGCAGCAGCGCCCCCAGGAGCUGGGAGAGUUGAGGGUGCUGGGCAGAGAUGAGACAGGGCGCCUCCGUGUGGUCUGGACCGCCCAGCCUGACACCUUUGCCUACUUCCAACUGCGCAUGCGGGUGCCCGAGGGGCCGGGGGCACAUGAGGAAGUGCUGCCAGGGGACGUCCGCCAGGCUCUGGUGCCUCCACCCCCUCCUGGAACCCCGUAUGAGCUGUCACUUCAUGGGGUCCCUCCUGGGGGCAAGCCCUCUGACCCCAUCAUCUACCAAGGCAUUAUGGACAAGGAUGAGGAGAAGCCUGGGAAGUCCUCAGGCCCACCACGCCUGGGUGAGCUGACGGUGACAGACAGGACCUCCGACUCCUUGCUCCUGCGCUGGACGGUCCCCGAGGGCGAGUUUGACUCCUUCGUGAUCCAGUACAAAGACAGGGACGGGCAGCCCCAGGUGGUGCCCGUGGAAGGACCCCAGCGCUCGGCCGUCAUCACCUCCCUGGAUCCUGGCCGCAAGUACAAAUUUGUCCUGUAUGGGUUUGUUGGCAAGAAGAGGCAUGGUCCGCUGGUGGCUGAAGCCAAGAUCUUGCCUCAGAGUGACCCAAGUCCAGGGACUCCACCCCACCUGGGAAACCUGUGGGUGACAGACCCUACCCCAGAUUCACUGCACCUCUCCUGGACUGUCCCUGAGGGCCAGUUUGACACCUUCAUGGUCCAGUACAGGGACAGGGAUGGACGGCCCCAGGUGGUACCUGUGGAAGGGCCCGAGCGUUCAUUUGUUGUCUCCUCACUGGACCCUGACCACAAGUACAGAUUCACUCUGUUUGGAAUUGCGAACAAGAAGCGGUAUGGCCCCCUCACGGCCGAUGGCACCACUGCUCCAGAGAGGAAAGAGGAGCCCCCCCGCCCUGAGUUCCUGGAGCAGCCCCUCCUGGGGGAACUGACAGUGACCGGCGUGACCCCAGACUCCUUGCGUCUCUCAUGGACAGUGGCCCAGGGCCCCUUCGACUCAUUCAUGGUCCAGUACAAGGAUGCACAGGGGCAGCCCCAGGCAGUGCCUGUUGCGGGGGAUGAGAAUGAGGUUACUGUCCCCGGCCUGGAUCCCGACCGGAAGUAUAAGAUGAACCUCUACGGGCUUCGUGGCAGGCAGCGUGUGGGGCCCGAGUCUGUGGUGGCCAAGACUGCUCCUCAGGAGGAUGUGGACGAGACCCCCAGCCCCACAGAACUGGGCACGGAGGCCCCGGAGUCCCCCGAGGAGCCGCUCCUGGGGGAGCUGACAGUGACAGGAUCCUCCCCUGAUUCGCUGAGCCUCUUCUGGACCGUCCCCCAGGGCAGCUUCGACUCUUUCACCGUGCAGUACAAGGACAGGGAUGGGCGGCCCCGGGCGGUGCGUGUUGGGGGCAAGGAGAGUGAGGUCACCGUGGGAGGCCUAGAGCCCGGGCACAAGUACAAGAUGCACCUGUACGGCCUCCACGAGGGGCAGCGCGUGGGCCCGGUGUCCGCCGUGGGCGUGACAGCCCCACAACAAGAAGAGACCCCUCCAGCCACUGAGUCCCCGCUGGAGCCACGCCUAGGAGAGCUGACAGUGACAGAUGUGACCCCCAACUCUGUGGGCCUCUCCUGGACAGUCCCCGAGGGCCAGUUUGACUCCUUCAUAGUCCAGUACAAGGACAAGGACGGGCAGCCCCAGGUGGUGCCGGUGGCGGCAGACCAGCGAGAGGUCACAGUCUACAACCUGGAGCCUGAGAGAAAAUAUAAGAUGAACAUGUAUGGACUACAUGAUGGGCAACGCAUGGGCCCCCUGUCUGUGGUCAUCGUGACGGCUCCCCUCCCACCAGCCCCAGCCACAGAGGCCUCCAAGCCUCCCCUGGAGCCACGCCUAGGGGAGCUGACAGUGACGGAUAUAACCCCUGACUCUGUGGGCCUCUCAUGGACAGUCCCUGAGGGUGAAUUCGACUCCUUUGUGGUUCAGUACAAGGACAGGGACGGGCAGCCCCAGGUGGUGCCCGUGGCUGCAGAUCAGCGGGAGGUCACUAUCCCUGACCUGGAACCCUCCCGCAAGUACAAGUUCCUGCUCUUUGGGAUCCAGGAUGGGAAACGACGCAGCCCAGUCUCUGUGGAGGCAAAGACGGUUGCCCGAGGUGACGCCAGCCCAGGGGCCCCACCCCGCCUUGGGGAGCUGUGGGUGACAGACCCCACCCCAGACUCACUGCGCCUCUCCUGGACGGUUCCUGAGGGCCAGUUCGACUCUUUUGUGGUCCAGUUCAAGGACAAAGACGGGCCCCAGGUGGUGCCCGUGGAGGGCCAUGAGCGCUCUGUCACUGUCACCCCUCUGGAUGCCGGCCGCAAGUACAGAUUCCUCCUCUAUGGCCUCCUGGGCAAGAAGCGCCAUGGCCCUCUCACUGCCGACGGCACCACGGAAGCCCGGAGUGCUAUGGAUGAUACUGGAACAAAGCGUCCCCCAAAACCCCGUCUGGGGGAGGAGCUGCAGGUGACCACCGUGACCCAGAACUCCGUGGGCCUCUCCUGGACAGUCCCUGAGGGCCAGUUUGACUCCUUUGUGGUCCAGUACAAAGACAGGGACGGGCAGCCCCAGGUGGUGCCCGUGGAGGGCAGCCUCAGGGAGGUCAGCGUGCCGGGCCUGGACCCUGCCCACAGGUACAAGCUGCUGCUCUACGGGCUGCACCACGGCAAGCGUGUGGGCCCCAUCUCGGCCGUCGCCAUUACUGCCGGCAGGGAAGAAACGGAAACUGAGACCACGGCCCCGACCCCUCCAGCGCCUGAGCCCCACCUCGGGGAGUUGACAGUGGAGGAGGCCACGUCACACACCCUGCAUCUCUCCUGGAUGGUGACUGAGGGAGAAUUUGACUCCUUCGAAAUCCAGUACACAGAUAGAGACGGGCAACUCCAAAUGGUCCGCAUAGGAGGUGACCGGAAUGACAUCACCCUCUCUGGCCUGGAAUCCGACCACAGAUACCUGGUGACCCUGUAUGGUUUCAGUGAUGGGAAGCAUGUAGGUCCUGUCCAUGUCGAGGCCCUGACAGUCCCGGAGGAGGAGAAGCCUUCAGAACCUCCCACCGCAACCCCCGAGCCCCCCAUCAAGCCUCGCCUGGGGGAGCUGACCGUGACAGAUGCCACCCCUGACUCCCUCAGCCUGUCCUGGACAGUUCCCGAGGGACAGUUUGACCACUUCCUGGUCCAGUACAGGAAUGGAGAUGGGCAGCCCAAGGCAGUGAGGGUGCCAGGGCACGAGGAAGGGGUCACCAUCUCGGGCCUGGAGCCAGACCAUAAAUACAAGAUGAACCUGUACGGCUUCCACGGUGGCCAGCGCAUGGGCCCUGUGUCUGUCGUCGGGGUGACAGCUGCAGAGGAAGAGACCCCCAGCCCCACAGAACCCAGCAUGGAGGCCCCGGAGCCCGCUGAGGAGCCGCUCCUGGGGGAGCUAACAGUGACAGGAUCCUCCCCUGACUCGCUGAGCCUCUCCUGGACCGUCCCCCAGGGCCGCUUCGACUCCUUCACCGUGCAGUACAAGGACAGGGACGGGCGGCCCCAGGUGGUGCGUGUUGGGGGCGAGGAGAGUGAAGUCACCGUGGGGGGCCUGGAGCCUGGGCGCAAGUACAAGAUGCACCUGUACGGCCUCCACGAGGGGCGGCGCGUGGGCCCAGUGUCUGCUGUGGGCGUCACGGCCCCCGAAGAGGAGUCCCCUGAUGCUCCUCUUGCAAAGCUGCGCCUAGGGCAGAUGACAGUGAGAGACAUCACCUCCGACUCCCUCAGCCUCUCCUGGACAGUCCCCGAGGGCCAGUUUGACCAUUUCUUGGUCCAGUUUAAGAAUGGGGACGGGCAGCCCAAGGCGGUGCGGGUGCCGGGACACGAGGAUGGGGUCACCAUCUCGGGCCUGGAGCCAGACCACAAGUACAAGAUGAACCUGUACGGCUUCCACGGUGGCCAGCGCGUGGGCCCCGUGUCUGCUGUUGGUUUAACUG